ACUUGCGCGGCCAGAGAGGGGCAGGUGCUGGGCGGCGGCUGACGGGCGCAGCACCCUAGGCCCAGUGUCUGGCUCCAGCCCCGCAUCCGGCGCCGGCCCCGCAUCCAGCUCUGGCCCUGCGACAAUAGAGUCCGGAAGUGCAGGCAAAGCGGCUCCCGGGAGCGCCGCGCGGUCCUGCGCGGGAUCAGCGAGGGCCGCGCCCCGGCGGGCGGGCGGCAUGGCUGCAGUGCUGGCUCUCAGGGUGGUCGCGGGGUUGGCGGCCGCAGCGCUGGUGGCCAUGCUCUUGGAGCACUACGGCCUGGCGGGCCAGCCCUCGCCGCUGCCGCGCCCCGCGCCCCCCAGGAGGCCGCACCCUGCGCCAGGGCCCGGAGACAGCAACAUCUUCUGGGGCCUGCAGGUGACGCGGCGGGAAGCCGGGCCGGGAGGCAGAUAUCCGACAUUCACCUGAGCAGGUUUCGAGAUCCAGGCAGAGCGGUAGACUUAGAGAAAUUCUGUUCUGAAACUAUUGACAUCAUUCAACCAGCUCUCGUCCUAGCAACAGGAGACCUGACAGAUGCCAAAACAAAGGAACAGUUGGGAUCCAGGCAGCAUGAGGUAGAAUGGCAAACCUACCAGGGUAUUCUGAAGAAGACAAGAGUCAUGGAAAAAACCAAGUGGCUGGAUAUCAAAGGAAAUCAUGAUGCAUUCAAUAUUCCAAGUCUGGACAGCAUCAAGAAUUAUUACAGGAAAUAUUCUGCUGUACGUAGAGAUGGCUCUUUCCAUUAUGUCCACAGUACUCCCUUUGGCAACUAUUCGUUCAUCUGUGUAGAUGCCACUGUAAAUCCAGGGCCUAAGAGACCCUAUAAUUUCUUUGGAAUUUUAGAUAAGAAAAAGAUGGAGGAGCUCUUAUUACUGGCCAAGGAAAGCAGUCGGAGCAACCAUACAAUUUGGUUUGGACACUUUACAACAUCCACUAUUCUUUCUCCAUCACCAGGAAUCCGGUCAAUAAUGAGUUCGGCUAUAGCUUAUUUGUGUGGACAUCUCCAUACACUUGGUGGACUGAUGCCUGUUUUGCACACUCGUCACUUCCAGGGCACUUUGGAACUUGAGGUGGGAGACUGGAAGGAUAAUAGGAGGUACCGGAUUUUUGCUUUUGAUCACGACCUCUUUAGCUUUGCAGAUUUGAUCUUUGGGAAGUGGCCUGUGGUUCUUAUCACCAAUCCUAAAUCACUCCUUUAUAGUUGUGGUGAACAUGAACCACUAGAAAGACUUCUUCACUCAACACACAUCAGAGUCUUGGCCUUUUCCUUAUCCUCCAUUACUUCUGUCACAGUUAAGAUUGAUGGAGUUCAUUUAGGCCAGGCUGUUCAUGUGUCUGGUCCCAUUUUCGUACUGAAGUGGAAUCCUAGAAACUACAGUAGUGGGACACAUAACAUAGAAGUAAUCGUCCAGGAUUCUGCUGGAAGAAGUAAGAGUGUUCACCACAUAUUUUCUGUUCAAGAGAAUAAUCAUCUCAGUUUUGAUCCCCUGGCAUCAUUUAUUCUCCGUACUGAUCACUACAUCAUGGCCCGGGUCCUUUUUGUGCUGAUUGUGCUGAGCCAGCUCACCAUUCUCAUUAUUUUUAGAUAUCGAGGAUACCCAGAGCUUAAAGAACCUUCAGGGUUUAUAAAUCUGACCUCAUUUUCUCUUCAUGUCUUGAGCAAAAUAAACAUCUUCUACUAUUCUGUGUUGUUGUUGACCCUGUAUACAGUGCUGGGUCCAUGGUUUUUUGGUGAAAUCAUUGAUGGCAAAUUUGGUUGCUGCUUUUCCUUUGGGAUAUUUGUUAAUGGACAUUUCCUACAAGGCAGCAUAACAUUUAUAAUUGGAAUUCUCCAGCUGGCGUUUUUUAACAUCCCCUUGAUGGCUUACAUGUGUUGGAGCUUGCUGCAGCGGUGCUUUGGUCACAACUUCAGGUCUCAUCUCCAUCAAAGAAAAUACUUGAAAAUUAUGCCUGUUCACCUACUUAUGCUACUGCUGUACAUCUGGCAGGUUUAUUCCUGCUACUUUCUUUAUGCAACAUACGGCACCCUAGCUUUUUUAUUCUCCCCUUUGCGGACCUGGUUGACACUGCUGACACCUGUUCUCAUUCGUUAUGUGUGGACACUGAACUCCACCAAGUUUGGAAUCUUCAUGGUGCAGUUAAAAAGCCACCUGAGCUCCUGAAGGCCAUGUCUCACCACUGGCAGCUGGGCAGAAGCCCAGCCUCUGUGUCUGUAGCCCAGGCCUCUACCCCAGUAGCAGGUGGAGGGCCAGGAUUGGUGGGUGAGCUUUAGGGAGCAGCUGCUCGUUUGGAGUCCUGGACGUUGGAGGGAUUACCCACUACUGAUACCUGCAGAAUGGACUGCAGAAAAGUCUCAAAAAUAAUGCCUUUAUUCCUUCCCUCCCUAAGGAGGCAAAGAGUUGAUUUACCUUUGUGAAGAGAAAACCCUUAUCUAGGACAUCCACAGGGUAGAGGUUGGGUGUGUGUACGGGAGUGUCUGAGGCCCAGUGUGUUUUUUAGGGUUACCCCAUGUAAAGCACUUACCGCUGUGCUUGGAAUUCAGCAGCUGUCAAAGGUGCAAUUUCAGGGGCAGGGAACCUUUGAGGAUCUGGGCCCGACCCUCACUACCCCUGAGAUAUUAGUUCCCAGGCCUGUUUUCCCACAGGAUUGUGGGCUCUCUGCUUCCUUAGUCGGAAGUGUUUUCAACUAAUCAAAUAAAUGAAUGAAUGAUGAAUAAGAAA